GGGUGGGGGGGCGGGAGUGAGGCCUGGGCGGGGAGCUGCCACGGGCCUGCGGGUGAGGGGAGCGACCCAGCCCGUGGGUGGUGAGGGGGGCUCCGGUUCGGGGAAGCAAGGGGGUGAGGCCCGGGCCCGAGGGCGAGAGAGUGAGGCCCGGGCAAAGAGGGUUGAGGCAUGAAACCCGGGCCGGGAGUGAGGUUUUGGGCCCGCGGGGCCGGGGUGAGGCGGAGGCCGAAUCCAUGCGUCUGAGGAGACGCGGGCAAGAGCUGGGGUCGGCGCUUGAUUACCCGGACGCCGCUGGACCUGGCCGCACGCCGCAAUCUAGCAGGCGUCGGGGAUCCAGGGCCGCUUUGAGGAGCCUGGCUUCGGAUUUCGCAUGUGGUGGUACAGUGGGAGCUAUUCUGACAUGUCCACUGGAAGUUGUAAAAACACGACUGCAGUCAUCUUCUGUGACGCUUUAUAUUUCUGAAGUUCAGCUGAACACCAUGGCUGGAGCCAGUGUCAACCGAGUAGUGUCUCCCGGACCUCUUCAUUGCCUAAAGGUGAUCUUGGAAAAAGAAGGGCCUCGUUCCUUGUUUAGAGGACUAGGCCCCAAUUUAGUGGGGGUAGCCCCUUCCAGAGCAAUAUACUUUGCUGCUUAUUCAAACUGCAAGGAAAAGUUGAAUGAUGUAUUUGAUCCUGAUUCUACCCAAGUACAUAUGAUUUCAGCUGCAAUGGCAGGUUUUACUGCAAUCACAGCAACCAACCCCAUUUGGCUUAUAAAGACUCGGUUACAGCUUGAUGCAAGGAACCGCGGGGAAAGGCGAAUGGGUGCUUUUGAAUGUGUUCGUAAAGUGUAUCAGACAGAUGGACUAAAAGGAUUUUAUAGGGGCAUGUCUGCUUCAUAUGCUGGUAUAUCAGAGACUGUUAUCCAUUUUGUUAUUUAUGAAAGUAUAAAACAAAAACUACUGGAAUAUAAGACUGCUUCUACAAUGGAAAAUGAUGAAGAGUCUGUGAAAGAAGCAUCAGAUUUUGUGGGAAUGAUGCUAGCUGCUGCCACCUCAAAAACUUGUGCCACAACUAUAGCAUAUCCACAUGAAGUUGUAAGAACAAGACUACGUGAAGAGGGAACAAAAUACAGAUCUUUUUUUCAGACUCUAUCUUUGCUUGUUCAAGAAGAAGGUUAUGGGUCUCUUUAUCGUGGUCUGACAACUCAUCUAGUGAGACAGAUUCCAAACACAGCCAUUAUGAUGGCCACCUAUGAAUUGGUGGUUUACCUACUCAAUGGAUAGCAGCACGAGGACUGCUGUACUGCAAAAAAAGAAGACCAAAAGAUUACAGUGGACCAUGGGAUACAGAAGCCAGCAUGGCAGACAGAAGAAAAAUAGUUUGGGAACAUGUAACUAUUCUAAGUGGAAGUUUUGUUGUAGGAAUUAUAGUAAUCACACCACAUUACUUGGCCUUUCGGUAAUGUGAAAAAAAAAAAAAACCUCAGAGCCUCCAAGGAAAUGCCUUUAGAAGCACUCCUCUCUCAAAAUUGCCAUUUUCUCUACCAUGUCCCCCAGACACAGUUGGGUUUUGUUGAUUUAUGGCAGUCUUCUAAACAAAGCCAUCCUUAAUUUUACAUACUGUAUUGUAACUAUCCAAAGAUAGUAUUGGCAGUCAUAAAUUUAUAACUUCUGGCCUUUGUUUAAUUCCAGUAAAAUAACAGCAAUGACAAUGAGAUCGUCAGUAUUAUUUUCACAUUUCCCUGAGAGGACCUGGCACAAUAUUUUAAAUUUAAUUAUUUGGCAGUAGUCACUGUUUUUGACAACCAAUGAAAUAGCGUCUAAAUAUCUUGUAUAUUUUUUAGCAUCAAAAUGUUUUGGUUUCCACUGCUGACAGGUGCUUGUUGUUUAGCCUAAUGUGGAUAUUUAAAUUGUUAACAUACCAAACACACAUGGUAAUAGUUUGGGACAAAAUAACUAGUAAAAUGUUGAUUUCUCGGCUUUUUCACUGACUGCGGCAUGUCCUCGUGUCUUCUCUGAUUUUGUGGUACAUGAAUGAAUGCAUUUAUCUUUUUAGUGACUUACUAGUUACGAACUUGAAUUAUCACCUCUUUGUCAUACUUAAGUAUCAUUUACAUAAAGUGUAAAAGAUUUUUUCACUUUUGAAUCUUUACCUACUUGCUUUCACAUUAAGAAUUUGAACUUUUGAGUUUUUUCCAGGUCUAUAUAUAAUAGAUUACAUUUAUUUUGUAAAGAAAAUAGUAAUUUAAAGUUUUGCCAUUUUAAGGUGACAAUAUUUGGGACAGUAUAAAUAUUAUAGACAAGGGCCCCCUUGCUGUCUGCUUUAGCAGGUAGUGACAUUAAUUGACUUAUAGUUUUGUGUAAAUGAACAAACUGCUUUUGACAAGAAAUUUAUUCUGUCCUAGUUUCCUGCGUGGUAAAUCAUAGAAAGAUUCAAGUUCAUUUGGGUUAAAUGUGCUAAUAGGAUGUAGCUUUUAAAUUCUGCUAUUGAGUCAGCUGUACCUUUUAAUACUUUAAAUGUGUUAUUUGUAUGGCCCUUAUAAAGGUGUUUGCUGUAAUUCUGUUAAAAGACUUCGCCUAUGCCAUACUGGUGUAUAAAAACUGCCGCAAUUGGACGCCGGUGUGGUACUCAUUUCAGUAUACCUGAACUGUACAUUUUGUGCAAUGGCUUUAUCUAAAAGAAUGACGCUUCGUGAAAGCACUUUGUGGCCUUUUUUGGGGGGGAGGGUGAGAGAGUAGGAGAGAAUACCAUGUUAAGAUUAAAAAAAAAAACAAAAACAUUGGUCACGUAUUAGGCAGAAACAGUGUUCAUAACAUUUUUCUGGGUUUUAAAUAUGUUGUUUCGGAUAUCCUUAAUAUAAAUGUUUUAGGUAUUCUGUGUACCCUGUCGUACCCCCAACAUUAUAGAAUAUUGCAGCGUGUCAUUGCAAGCUUUCUCUGCUGUCACCAGUGAAACAUAGUGCCCUGUUAAAUUCCCCCACUUUAACUUCCUUGUGAUCAACAGUAACUGGAUGUUUUUGAGGUGCUCAAUUGGAAUAAAAAUAUUCCAAUCUAUUUGGAGACCAAAGGCAAAAUCAGUUUUCUUACCUUUGGAAUUAUUCGUACCUUUUAUGGUAAAUUUCAGCUUUGACAUGUAUUAUGAGGAACGUACCAAAAACCGGUUUGUAACAAAUCUGUAGAGAAGGUCUGAAUCUAUCGUGUUUGCCUUUUCAGGUGCCAUUUCUACUGCCUAAUACAGUGCCAUUUGCCUUGUGAAGACCCAUAAACAUUCAUUGUGUUGAAUGUAAGAUAGAGACUCUCCCUAGUCUUACUGAUCUCAGUACCCCACAAAUGAUUAAGAAUGAUAUGAAAACCAGCAGCUAAGGAACAUCUUAUUAUUUAGUUGUAGCAUAUUCAUAACAAGUGUCCUUCAAGGAUAAACAUAUAUUCUCUAUUUGUAUUUAGCAAGUAAAACUUGUGUUGACCUUUAGUGCAUUAUAUUCAGCUUUUAACAGUAUUAUGUAUGUACUGGAAAGCAAAGAAAUCUUAGAGUCUUGGACAUUGUUUAUUUGUGCAACAACUAGAAAGGAGCAAUGAAGUUUAUUUCAGUUGUAUUUUUCCCUAAGCACAAUCUGCAAUAGUUUAUGUAUGACAGAGAUAAUUCAAAAAGGAAAACUAUAUAUAAAAGUUGUAUAUAAAGUUUGUCUCUGAAAUAUUUCUUUGAAGUUUUUAAAAAAUCGACUCAUGUUUAAAAACAAAAACACAUAUUCAGAGCAUUGGACUUUUUUAACUUGUUUUCAUCUGUUUAUCAUGACUUUUUUAUUUCUGGUGUAGAGUCCACAUUAUUUAGUUUGUUGUACUUUUAAAUUUCAAAGUUCAAAUCUGAAGAAUUAGCGUUUGUGAUUUCGGGAUACCAUGCAGUGGUUUUAAUCCCAGGAAAAAAACUAUCACCAAAAGUUCGUUUGAUUCUCAUUAUGUAACUUUGUAGAACCAUCCUUUCUAGAUGGGUCCACCACAGUGAAUUUGUAACUUUGAAGUCAGGAUAGAAUAUCAUUAGAUUAUCUGUGAGAUAGCAUUACUAUGUUAGGACCAGCAGAGUUUGGGUUGGUAAAAAUAAUGUUUGCUCUAUUACUGGGUUACAGACAUUUCAGCAUUUUUAGGUUGGUUUUAAAUCACUAAAAAUAUUUAUUCGGAUUUGAAGGAUUUAAGUGCUAAAAAUCAAUCCAUUUCUUGCCCUUCAAUAAUUGUCCAUGCCUGCCUUUUGUUGUUUACAUGCUCUUCUGCCCAGACUGUUAGUAAUCUAGGGACCCCCUUUGGAGCUGAUAAGUACAGUUCAGCCUUUUCUCCUCAAAUAUAUAAUGACUUUAACAUUCCUAAGAAUAUAGGUAUUUCUGAAUGAUUUAAAUUUGAGGAAUUUUAAUACAUAAAAUACAAUGUACAAACUUUCUGCCCACUCAGAUCUCUUCUCCAUCAUGUACUUAGUAUUUCCCAUUAACCUACACACUGAUUUUUAUGCUACUCCUUGUAGAAACAAAAUUCUGGUUUGACUCAGUUUUUGUGUUUAUAAACUUUUGGAAUGUGUACCCCGUUUAUGUGAAGAAUUAUGACCUAUCAGUCAUAGCUAAAUAGUGAACCUCAAAAGUGUUAACUUUUGACUAUUCAUGUGAGGUUUGGUAUCUUGCAUUUAUGUACAUGGCUGUAAAUUAUGUGCAUUUACUCUGUAUUUAUGUUAUCUAGCUGACUUUUACUUGAAUUGUUCAAAUUUUAAAAAUUAAAAUACGCUCAUGAAAAUAUGGCUUUUUCUGUAAUAUAUCAACAUUUUAUUGAGAACAUAAUCACACUUUUUUGGAUUAUCCUAUGUGUGGAACAAAAAUCCAUUGCCAUUUUCAGGUUAAGUUUUAGGCUCGCUUGAUUCAGUCAGCAAACCUUAUCUUGAGCACUUUGUAUCUGUUAGAUCUAGUGAUGUCUGAAGGAACCCAAAGGUCAAGUAAUCCAACUCCCUCAUAGUGUACAAAGAAAUCUUGCAUAUCUUCCACAGGUUUAUUGACUUUUAUCCAACACUUUUCAUGUUUUAAUUUCAGCCUUUGUGAAAGUUGAUAUUAAAAAUACAGAGGUGAGAACUUGUUAGAAUAACCAAAUGAAUCCACAUAAUGUUAGAUCAAAAUACAAAUGACAAAGAUAAAAUGCUAUGUAGUGCCUACCCUCUUUACAUUUUGUCUAUUUUAUUUAAGUUUUUCUGUAUUGUAGUUAACAUCAAACAUUGUCCAGUCUUGAGGAAACCAGGACGAAAUAUAUUUUGUAUUUCAACAUUGACAUAAAUCUGAAAUUGUUGGUUCUACUAAUAGUACUCUGCACUGAAGGCACUGGCAAAAUAAUGGUUAAAAUUGAGCACAGGUGUUCCAAGUUGUGUGUGUGUGUUUAUUACUGAACAUUGGGAGCCGUGAUAGGGAAGUAAUUUGUGAGUUCAUGAUUUCUUAAGGUUCUAGUGUGACAUUUAUACACUGAUAAAACUCAGGCAAGCAAAAUGUAAUUAAAUGUUCCCCCUGCCCCCCCCCCCUUUUAAUAUAUAUACACGGAGCUUCACUCUUGUCACCCAUGCUGGAGUGCAAUGACAUGAUCUCAGGUCACUGCAACCUCUGCCUCCCGGGUUCAAGCGAUUCUGCCUCAGCCUGACUUCCCUUCUGUUUCUUUAUUUUCGCACUGUGUAGACCAGCUGACUGCCUUAAUAUGUAUUGAAUCAAUUCAAGAUUUAUGUUCAUAGAGUGCUGUGUUUAUACAGUGGUGUCAUGUGAUUUCUUAAUAGCCUAUAGAUCCAAUAAAUACAGAGGAAUAUUAGUUACAACUGGA